AGAUCUCGGCGCGCCCCUGAGGAGUUUCUGUGGGAAGAUUUUCUGUUUUCCAGGUUUCCCAAGGGAAACGAAGAAAGGGAGGAGGAUAAUCAAUGACUGAACCUCUAAUAGAUGUUGGACGACGUUAAAAAAAAAAUGUAUCGGCCCUACCCUCGAGGAUUUGACAAAUUAGACUGACCAGAGUAAUAAGAGAUACAGGCAGAAGAGGAGACAUAGACACACACAGAGGAGAAGAUGAUGUGAAAAGGGAGGCAGAGAUCACAGUGGUGUGGCUACAAGCCAAGAAAUACCGAAGCCAUCAGAAGUUGGAAGAGCCACCAAGAGUGCUGAACAAUCAUCUGAGGACAUCAUUGGGUAUCACUGGCAAAGAGAAGAGAUGAAGAAAAGAUAAGAGAAAGAAAUGAAAGUGGAAGAGGGCAGAAAAAGAUAAACAAAAGUUAGGAGAGUUUUCAGGAGGAGAAAAUAAAGAGAAGACAGAGAAGGAAGUAUCUGCCUUCCUUCUCCAGGGUUACCUUCUUCUUAUAAACCUGUUCAUGACUCAGUCCAGGCUCCUCAUCCCUUCACUUUCAUGCCCCCAAAUGCACUACCGCAAAUACAAGACUGGUGUGUGGGGUACCAAAAAAGCCUAUGAACUUAAAAGGGAGAGAAAAAACAAUAUUGGCUCUGAGACCCACAUGGAUUCACCACCAGUAGCAUACGUUGAUGCCAUGCGACUGGGAUAUAAUCUGCUGCUAACAUACUUUGGUGUCAUGUGACUUGGAUACAUUUCCCAGUGGGAAAGGCCAGAUGACAACCUGAAACUCAGCCAAGCUUGCAGCUGUGGUCGCUGGUGAAGUCAACUCCAGCAAACCGGAGGCAUUAAUAAUCUUCCUGAGGUGCUCCUCUCUUUUUCCAAUUCCCACCUUGAUAGAGGGGUAUCUCAAAGUGGGCGAAUCAAAUUGAGAAGAACUGGGAACAGCCAACAACCUCCCACCACAGCACAGUUAAGGGAUUCUGUUCCAUCAAGACAGCCAUCAGCCAAUCAGUUGUCUGCCAACCCAUCAUCUGCCACCCCAUCCUUAGUCAACAAAGCAGGAAUCAACUGGGCAUGAACCAAUCAGGCACGAACCAAUCAAGUUUAUCAGACUCGAACCAAGCAGGCAUAAACCAGCCAAGCACAAACUCACUUGGUAUGAACCAAAUGGACAUGAACCAAGGGAGUGCAAGCCUAUAUGAAAUGAACCAAGUGGACAUGAAACAACCAAGCAUGAGCCAAGCUGGCAUGAGGCAAUCAGGUACAAACCUACCAGACAUAAACCAACCCGACAUGAAACAACCAGACACAUGGCAAUUAGGUAGGAGCCAACCAGGCAUGCUGCAACAAGAACUGAGCCAACUAGUCCUGAGCAAAGCAGGCAUAAGCCAACCAGACCCAUCGCAACCAGGCCCAAGCCAAUCAGGCCCCAGCCAAUCACGCAUGAGGCAAAUAGGCACGAACCAAUCAGGUAUGAGCCAACCAGUGAUGCAGCAACUAGACAGCCAGUCAGGUGGGAGCCAACCAAGCAUGAGACAAGUAGGCACCAGCCAAUUAGGCACAAGCCAAAUAGGCAUGAGCCAACCAGGCACAUGGCAAACAGGACUGAGCCAACCAGUCCUGAGGCAACCAAACAUGAGUCCACCAGGCAUGUGGCAACCAGGCGUGCAACAACCAGGCAUCAGCCAGCAAGUCCCAAGCCACCCAGACAUGAGUCAACCAGGCAUGAGCCAGCAAGUCCCCAGCCAACCAGGCAUAAGGCAACCAGACACUAGCCAAUCAUGUAAGAACCAAACAGACAUGAGCCAACCAGACGCAAACCAAUCAAGUUUAUCAGAUUCCAACCAAACAGGUAUAAUCCAGCCAAGCCCAAGCUUACUUGGUAUGAACCAAAUGGACAUGAACCAAUGGAGUGCAAGCCUAUAUGAAAUGAACCAAGUGGACAUGAAACAACCAAGCAUGAGCCAAGCUGGCAUGAGGCAAUCAGGUACAAACCUACCAGACAUAAACCAACCUGGCAUGAAACAACCAGGCACAUGGCAAUUAGGUAGGAGCCAACCAGGCAUGUGGCCACAAAGCCUGAGCGAACUAGUCCUGAGUGAAGCAAGCAUAAGCCAACCAGGUCCACCGCAACGAGCCCCAAGCCAAUCAGGCCCCAGACAAUCAAGCACGAGCCAAGCAGGCACAAACCAAUCAGGUAUAAGCCAACCAGUGAUGUGGCAACUAGACAUGAGACAGUCAGGUGGGAGCCAACCAAGCAUGAGACAAGUAGGCACCAGCCAAUCAGGCACAAGCCAAAUAGGCAUGAGCCAACCAGGCACAUGGCAAACAGGCCUGAGCCAACCAGUCCCGAGGCAACCAAACAAGAGUCCACCAGGCAUGUGGCAACGAGGCAUGUGGCAACCAGGCAUGAGCCAGCAAGUCCCCAGCCAACUAGGCAUGAGACAACCAGGCACUAGCCAAUCAAGUAAGAACCAAACAGGCAUGAGCCAUCCAGGCAGGGGCCAACCAGGCAUAUGGGAACCGGGGCCGAGUCAGCCAGGCCUGAGCCAACAAGACCUGAACCAAUUAGUGCUGAGCCAACCAGGCCUGAGUCAACCAGGCAGGAGCCAACCAAGUGUGAGCCAAAUGGGCAUGAGGCAAACAAGCAUGGAUUACUUUCAAAUAAGACAUGCAGAGGCUGGAGACUGCCCAGAAAUUUUGCGACUGAUUAAAGAAUUGGCUGCCUGUGAAAACAUGCUAGAUGCAAUGGAGUUAACAGCAGCUGAUUUACUCAGAGAUGGCUUUGGGGACAAUCCCCUUUUCUACUGCCUGAUUGCAGAAGUAAACGAUCAACAAAAACCAUCAGGCAAACUGACUGUUGGAUUUGCCAUGUACUACUUUACAUACGACUCAUGGACUGGCAAGGUACUUUACCUAGAGGACUUUUAUGUCACACAAGCUUACCAAGGCCUAGGUAUUGGAGCUGAAAUGCUGAAGAGGCUAAGUCAGGCUUCUAUCAACUACUAUACUAGUCGAGGGGCUUUAGACCUUUCCUCUGAGGAGGGCUGGCAUCUCUUCAGGUUUAACAGAGAAGAACUCCUGGACAUGGCAUGGGAAGAAUGAAAGAGGCUUUGUAACAACUCAUCCCAACACAGCCUCCAACAUUUGACUGUCACCUGAGUCUAACAGCAGUUUGACUUUGUUGUACAAUACAGCAAGUGAUCAUCACA